GUACGUCAUCGGCGACGGCUCCCGCCGGCUGGGCGUCCGGUGGCCGGUGUAGCAGAGCGGGAGCGGCGGGCGGCGAGCAGAGGAGCUAACAGGUGGGGGCACGGCACGCGGACGGACCCCCCCAAAGGCCGGGAGGAGGCGCGCGACGCGACCUUUCCUGAUCUCCCGGAGAAGCCUCCACUCCAUUGUCUCCUGGCCCCACCCUCCAUUGGGCACGCCCUUCACCUUAUCCCCCACCACUUAUUGGCUGCAGGUCACGCCCCUCCUCUAUUUCUGGUUCCCCAUUGGCUCUUCACCUUGUCCUCUCCGGGGCUUCUCUCCGCACAGGCCACACCCUCUCAUUUGUCACUAGACCCCGCCUUAAUAGUGGGGGGCUCCUCCCCCAUCCAUCCUUCAUUCAUUAUGCACCCAGUGCUGGGUGCUUGGUACACGGGGGUGAAUCAGACCCCAUUCCUGCCUUCGGGGAGUUCAGGGGAUUGUGGGAGGACACGGACCUAGACUCCAACAGUGACAGCUCUGAGUAAAGAAGUCGCCGAAGCAGUGGGACACUAGACGCGGGGAAGGCUUCCUGGAGGAAGUGAGGCCUAAACUGAGCCUUGAAGAAUGGUUAAGAGUUUGCUCCAGGAAUAUAUUGCAAAGGCAUUCUUGGCGGAAGGACCCGAGACGUGAAAAAAACAGGCGUAUUCUGGUAAUUUCGAGGAGAUGGAGAAGUAACAGCAUGUGUUUAUCCUGAUGGAAAGAGUCCAGUAGAGAGGAAGAGAUUGAUGAUGUAGGAGAGAGGAGAAAUGCUGGAAGUGAGUCACUGAGCAGGCAAGGGAGCUCAGCAGCUGGAGCCUCUCCAGAGGUCGACAGUGUGGGGAGUUGGAGUGACCCGGCUGGAUGUGACCCCCAGGACAGAAUGGUGCUGGACUCAGGGGCUCAGGCGUAUGAUCAGGCACCCCCCAGCCCGCCUACCAGUCCCCCAUCCCUGCGCCAUAGGCUGAAGCCCUCAGACCGAGAUGGGCCACCACUGUACCCCUGGUCUCAGUCCCUGGCCUUGCCCCUGGCUCUGGCAGUCCCCCCAGCGCUGCAGCCCCAGCCUGAGCAGCAGCCGUUCUCACAGAUGCUCCUGGGCCACCGUGGCCACAUGCGUCGCAGUGAGAGCACCUACUCUGUAAAUAGUACUGGCCGGCGGGGGCGUGGCACCCUGGGACGGCCUCCACCUGGACGGGGACGGAACCCAGGUGGGGGCACCCUGCGGCCUGCAGCCUCCCUGCCUCACAUUGCUAAGACUCAAAGGGAUGCAGGCCAUAUUGCCAGCAAGAGCCCCUGCAUGUUGGUGGCCCUGCGGCCAACCAACAUGGACCGUGAGCGAGACAAGUUCUUCCAGUCCCAUUACACCUACAAUCCACAGUUUGAGUACCAGGAGCCCAUGCCCACGGCUGUGCUGGAAAAGUACUGCGAGGCCUCUGGACAGUUCAUCCAUCAGGCAGUUGGCAUCAUUGAGGCUGUUCUGGAGAAGUUUGGAACCUAUGAACACUUUGAGGCUGCCACUGGGGGGCAGCUGCUCACCAAGUGCCAGAUAUGGUCGAUUGUGCGCAAAUACAUGCAGAAGGAGGGCUGCGCUGGGGAGGUUGUGGUGCAGCUGAGUGAGGACCUGCUGUCCCAGGCAGUGAUGAUGGUGGAGAACAGCCGGCCCACAUUGGCGAUCAACCUGACCGGAGCCCGCCAGUACUGGUUGGAGGGCAUGCUGCGGCAUGAGAUAGGCACCCACUACCUGCGGGGCGUGAACAACGCGCGCCAGCCGUGGCACAACGCGGAGGGCCGGCUGCGGUACGGGCUGCGGCCGGCGAACCCCACGGAGGAGGGCCUGGCCAGCCUGCACAGCGUGCUGUUCCGCAAGCAGCCGUUCCUGUGGCGCGCUGCACUGCUCUACUACACCAUCCACCGCGCCGCGCGCAUGUCCUUCCGUCAGCUCUUCCAGGACCUGGAGCGCUACGUGCAGGACGCCGAUGUGCGCUGGGAGUACUGCGUGCGCGCCAAGCGCGGCCAGACCGACACCUCGCUGCCAGGUUGUUUCAGCAAGGACCAGGUGUACCUGGACGGCAUCGUGCGCAUUCUGCGACAUCGCCAGACCAUCGAUUUCCCGUUGCUGACCUCACUGGGCAAGGUGUCCUAUGAGGAUGUGGACCACCUGCGGCCCCAUGGGGUGCUGGAUAAUACCCGGGUGCCCCACUUCAUGCAGGACUUGGCACGCUACCGGCAGCAGCUGGAGCACAUCAUGGCCACCAACCGGCUGGAUGAGGCGGAGCUGGGUCGCCUGCUACCCGACUGAUGUCCGUUGAGGGCUGCAGUCAGAGGCCCUGGACAGAAGCUCCAGAUAGGCCCCUAGAACAUGAAGCAGUUUGCUCUGUGCGUCCACGGCCUAGGUGUUUCUUGGGGGUGUUGGGAGGGCAGGAGCAUUCCUUGAGGAGGAGUGGCAACAUCAAAGUGUUUGUGUCCCUUGCCAGCCUCCCUGGGGUCUGGGGACCUGCAGCAGCAUGUCUGGCAAACUGAGUCGCCCUCCUGCCUCCAGCUCUCUGUUGAGCAGAGGGAAGGCAUGGGGGCAGGAAGAGAGCUGAGCAUUGAUGGGGAUGGGGGUGGUUUGGGAAUAGAAACUUGUUCUUGCAUGAGAUGGCUUUGGUUGUCCCAGUACUCCAGUCUCUCCCUUCCCUUACCUGGCCCCUUGGUGCUCCUUCAGCAUUUGUGCUGUCUACCUCUCACUGGGUCCUGGUGGGGGUCGGGCUCCCUUCUCCUGGGGUGAUUGAUGGCCUGAGCCUGGGGUCCUGGUAGUAGAGACCCAGCUGGCCUGGGGUCUGCUUUCCGACAUUUUGCCUCUCUCACUGGUCAUGUAUUUAUUCCAUAUUUAUAUGGUCUACUUCCUGUGGCUGGGAGCAGCAGCUCCUGAAGGUUCCGUGGGGGUGCGGGGGGUUGGACAGGACACUCCUUCUUGGAAGGCACCAAUUUUCCCAGCCCCACUCCCAUUACACACACACACACACACACACACACACACACACACACACACACACACACACACACACACACACACUGAUUCAGGCCUUGAGAGUCAAGCCCAAGAGCUCCCUUGGCCCUGUUCCCCACUCCCUCCACUGGCCUCUGCUGUUCCUGUCUUUGCUCACACCCUCACAGCUGCUCUCUGGCAGAGGUUGGCAUAGCCUAGGAGCAGCUGCAAUUGCACCUGAGGGACAGGCCCUAGAGUUUGGUGGCCCAAGUCCUGAACCCCUCUUAGACCAGGUGAGGUGCAGAGGUGGUUGCUGCUUCCAGUUUCCCUUCAGACUUAGCUGUGUGAACCCCACUCCUAUCCUUUGGCCUUAGUUUUCCCAUCUGUAAAACUCAGAAACGCAGUUGGAAAGUCCUUAUUCAUUUAGUAAGCGAAUAUAUUAUAAUAUGUAUAGAGCGCCUUUUGUGUAAGUCACUGGUCAGAAUCCUCACUGAGCUCCCAGUCCAGAGAGAAGCCAGACAAUUAAAACAGUAAUGACAAUGA